ACCCCUCGCUGACUCGCUUCGCUUCCCCGACGCGCUGGGUUCCCGGAGCGCAGAGCCCAGCGUUAGCGGGUGGGCUCCCCGAGGCCCCCUGCCCUCGCCGGGCUGCUCCAGGGUGUCGCUCCUCUGGCUGCUCCCGAAGGGGCUUCUGGCCCUGAGGACGGUGGUGCCAAGCGAACUUCAUUUUUAAAAAGAACUGGUGGAUGAGAAGAGCGAGCGAGGGCGAGCUAUGGACCCUGUGAGUCAGCUGGCCUCUGCGGGCACCUUCCGGGUGCUGAAGGAGCCCCUUGCCUUCCUGCGAGCCCUGGAAUUGCUUUUUGCAAUCUUUGCAUUUGCAACAUGCGGUGGCUAUUCUGGAGGCCUGCGGCUGAGUGUGGACUGCGUCAACAAGACAGAAAGUAACCUCAGCAUCGACAUAGCGUUUGCCUACCCAUUCAGGUUGCACCAGGUGACGUUUGAGGUGCCCACCUGCGAGGGAAAGGAACGGCAGAAGCUGGCAUUGAUUGGUGACUCCUCGUCUUCAGCAGAGUUCUUCGUCACUGUUGCUGUCUUCGCCUUCCUCUACUCUUUGGCUGCCACUGUCGUUUACAUUUUCUUCCAGAACAAAUACCGGGAAAACAACCGGGGCCCACUCAUUGACUUCAUUGUCACUGUAGUCUUUUCGUUCUUGUGGUUGGUGGGUUCAUCAGCUUGGGCAAAAGGACUGUCUGACGUCAAAGUUGCAACGGAUCCCAAGGAAGUAUUGCUACUAAUGUCAGCUUGCAAACAGCCAUCCAACAAAUGCAUGGCUAUCCACAGCCCUGUUAUGUCAAGCUUAAACACUUCUGUGCUUUCUGAAAUUCAAUCUGCGAAGGCACUUAAGAAGAGAGAAAGGGUUGCUACUCUGACUGGACUGUGAUUUCUGCUUUGGUGAGAUAGUAACCAUGAAAAUAAGCUCUGCAUUAGGGUCUCACAAUAAUUUUUAUUCAUUGCUGACCACACUUGUAAAUGAACACUUUGAGGUAUACGUUACCAUAUUUACUUAUACUUCUGUAGUUUGUUUAUAGACAGUAUUUAAUGAAAGCUAUUAAAACCCUGAUCUCAAAAUCUAACAGGACAAAAAUAAAAUUGCUUGAUAUGUUUGUUAGUUUAAUAACUAAUCUCCCAAUAAAUUAUGACGUUCUGCAUGGUUCUUCUAAUUCCACUUCUGAUAUAUCUAAUAAUUUUUAGACUAAAAGAUGGAAAUUAUGAAUGAAAAACAAUGUGAUGUGUCUCCUAAAACCAAAAUAAAGAAUGAAUUGAAACCAAAUAAUGUGAUGUGUGUGAAAGGACAGGUCCAGUGGUGCUGUAGUGAUGUAUCCAUAUCAGUUAACAGUCUUCUAGUUCCUAGUGACAGAAAACUCAAUUCAAACUGGCUAAGGCAAACCAAUCCUCAUAUCCCUAAAAUCUGUUUUUGCAGUCCACUUCUGGUACCAAUGUUUGUAUGCAUUAGAAUAAUCAAAGCUGAUUUUAACUACAACAGGAAAAAAGUAUUUGGAAGGAUAUUAAGUCGCUCAUACAACUUGAUGAAACCUGAAGAAACAGGUUCUAGAAAGAGCAGAAUCUAGAGCAGAAUGAGAGUUCUAGAUGUUCAGUACCAAAUAAUUGUUUCUUAGAGUUGCCAUUAGUGGAAAGUUUUACCUAACCUUGCAUUGCUCUGCUCAAAAUGCAAAGUUCCAGGAGAGAGCUCAAGCCAUUUGACCGAAACUUGGCUCUGCAAAGAAAAUCAGAUUUCUAUUACCAAAAGCAGGGGAAAGGACAUUAAUGAACCAAAACACAAUAUUUUUAUUACAAAUUGUUUGGCUUCAAAUCAUACUGAGCUAGCUUAUGCAAAAACUGAAAAUAGUUGGAAAGACAUUAAAAGUGUGUCUUCCCAGGGCAAAACCCAACAGCCAAGAACUGGAAGGCUGCCAGGAAGCUGGACAGUUCUCAUCCUCCAUCUCUCAUCUCUCUUUCUUUCUGUGUCCCUGUCCCUUUCUGCAUGUUUGUUACAUUAUUCUCUCUUUUCAGGUGAAACUUUAUUUCUUUUUUUUCAUCCACACAGCAGAAGAUAGCCACUCUGCAGUUUCUAAGUUUAUAUGUAUUUUUUAAAGACUGAACGGCUUGGACUGAAUGAAAAUCACUCAGGUCCAGUUGCAAAUUUCUGGUAGAGAGAAUCUCUUUUGCCCACCUUAGGCCAGAUGCCCACCUCAGUCUCAUCAGUUAUGAAUAGAGGGUUUGGAGGAUGAUGUAGUAGAAACGUGACUCAGAGAACACACUUUACUGGGCAAACAUAGGUUUUGGAGUAGGAGGCAUACCCAUACCACAAUAAAUGACCUCUACAAGUAAAUGAGUCAGGAAAUAAUAGUCAUAUUCUCUACCUUGGUAACAAAUUUACUAUCUUCAAAGCACUUUUUGGCACCUAUAAUUUUACAGUAACACUAAAAUGUAGGUAAGAUAUCCAGAUACUACAAAUACUGGGAGCUAAGGUAAACUCUCUAAUCCUUAGUUUUAUCAUCUGUAAAGUGGGGAUAAUUGUACAACAGACCUCAAUACUGUUGAAACAAUUCAGUGAGAUAAUCUAUAAAAAAAAUACUUAGCAUCAUGCCCAGCUUAUGGCAAAUGGUCAAUACAUGUCAACUGAAAAUGGCUACUAAAAUACGGUCAUUCCCAAAUGUCAUACAGUGUUAGAGCCUAAAUACAGAAGGAAGAAAUAAUGUUUUUAGUCUCUCAAUUUCUUUCAAAGUUUCACUGAGCACAAAUAGUUUGGCCAUAAUUUCAACUUCUGCUUCUCCAGCUUCACUCCAGACAAAUCUUAGUACAUCUUUUUAGACGAUCUAGAUCUUGUCUCCCCAUUGUUUGCAUGUUAUGUACAGUCUCUUUCAAUCUCUCUUUCUGUUGUCCCCAAGUCUGAGCUUGAAUCACAUUCUUACCCCAAUUUCAGUUCCAACAAAAUAGCAAAAAAGAGUUCAAGGGCCCAAGUGACCCUAAAAUGUGCCAGCCAAGAGAUCUGUGAUGCUAGAGUAAAAAAUCAGUACUCCUUAAAUAUGCCCAUUGAAAUGCCUUGUUUACGUUCUUACUUUUAAGUAGCAUUUCCUUGAUGUCUAAGUUUUUCUUUUUUAAAAUCCAAAUAGUAACAGGGAAAAGAGAAAGAUCAAUAGAUAGGAAAUAGCUAAAAUUACAUCCCUGGACAGAGCCAUGACUGAAAAGAUCCCUUGAUAAUUUUUCCUCCCCUCCCCCACCCUCCCCUCCACUCCCCUCCUCUCCUCUCCUCUCUUCUCUUCUCCUCUCUUCUCCUCUCCUUUUCUGUUUUCCUUUCCUUUUGUUUCCUUUUUUCUUUUUUUUUUUGAGACAGGGUUUUGCUCUGUCACCCAGGUGGGAGGUGCAGUGGUGCAAUCAUAGCUCACUAUAACCUGGAACUCUUGGGCUCAAGGGAUACUGCUGCCUCAGCCUUCCAAGUACCCCUUCUGAGUACCUGGGACUACAGGCAUGUGCUGCCAUGCUCAGCUAAUUUUUUUUUUUUUAAGAGACAAGGUCUUGCUAUGUUGCCCAGGCACCUCAAUAAUUUUUUAUACUCUUAUAUUGACAUACACUUGUAAAGGUGCAAUUUAAUCAAGAUCCCCCUUUUAACGGAAAAUAUUCUGGUUACCAUGCACAUGGUAAAAUGGUCCUGUAUGCAAAUUAGAGUUUUGUCAGUAGUUAACUAAUUUAUUUUGUUCAAGCAACUAUUAUACCUUAUUUACGUUUUGUAUCUCCCUCAGCAGGUAGCCUAGAGCAUGGCACAAAAUAGGUUCUCAAUUAGUGUAAAAAGUAAGGAAAGAGGAUGCAAGAGGAGAGAAGGAAGAAGGAGGGAGGUCUGUACAAACCAGUCUUUAAUUAGAUCAGUUGGGGGCCUAGAGUCUUGAUUUUGGCUAUUGUCUCAAGAACAUCGUCUCACUGUUUGUGCCUCAGUUCAAUUUAUGCUGCAGCAAAAAAAAAAAAAAAAAAAAAAAAAAAAAGUCUGCAAAGUACAAUUCACAGAAAUGUUUUAGAAAAUGAUUCAGAGCAUAGUUUACCAUUUAGUAAGUAUUUGCUAAUGUGUCCAGCACUGUCCAGCUACUUUACACACAUCCUCUUUAAUCCUCCCAACUACCUUCCAAGAAAGGAAUUCUUGUCUCCAUUCCAUACAAGAAACAAAACAAAAACAAAAAUGAAGUCUACAGACUAAAUGCCUUGUCCCAGGUAGCAGGGCAAGAAAGUACAGUCCCCAGGGUGCCUUUGAUUUCAAAGCCUAUAGAGAUUUCUCCAAGCCUAAGAUUCCAUUCAUGUGCUGCUAAAAUAUUGAAAUAUUUUGAUAGUCUCAGAUCCAAGUCUCCAAGGCCCAGCUUCUUGACUACACCAGUGCCCCCUCUGCCACCACUACCCACAGGCCACUGUGGAUCAUCUCACUGUCCAGAAACUAAGGGAUAGAUAUUGACCCAGCAAAGGACUUCCAGCACCCUACUCCAGGACCGUGGCCACUGCCCAAGUCCAUUUUGAUUGGUCAGCGUCACGCUAGGGGGUGAUGACUAAAUAUACUUUAAUGUUAUCACAGCUUUGCGUUAUACUACUGUUACCUGUCUCCAUUAGGGGGCUGUUAAAACAGACUGCCUGUAGUUAAUUCCCAAGUCAAUCAACCAGCCUUGGAAAAGGCUGCAGAACAAGUCAUGGAAUGAGGACUUCUGUUCGGGCCUCAUGCAAUAGCAAACCGUUCUGCUUCCAUCAAACCUGAGGCCCUGGGGAGGCGACACCCAGUCCUCUGGCUCACUGACACCCUCCUGGAGAGUAAGAGGAAUUUCCAUAGGAAAGUUUCACAUCCAGUUCUUAAGAAAAUAUUUUAUACUUCUCUGAAACCUGCACUUUAUUCACAGUCUGGUUUCAACAUUCACUUAUCCCUGUGAGAGGCACAGAAAGUGCAAUUAUUCGAACAGUCAACCUCUCAAUAUGCUAUCAUGCAUAUGCUUAUUUGCAUAUCACCUGUACCAUUGCUUACCCUAUAUUUUUAAUUGACUCACUUUCUUUAUAUGAUUACAACAAAUGGAAAAGCAAAAGCAGUAUCUCUAACCAUAAAGAGAAGAUAGCCUUAUAAAUGAAUGCACCAUUAUUAAAGUGAAAAUUCUCAACCCUGUGCCAUCUGGAAAUAAUCUUACACACCAUGAAGGAUACUUUAUUUGGAGAAUAAGUGAUGCCUUAAGUAAGGUUUCCAGUUAUGGAACCAGAAGAGAGUUUGGAUCACAGAUCUACUACUCAGCAAGCCACGCGACCUUAGACAAGCUUUCCACAUCUUUAAUGUGGGUAUGACAAUAGCAACUUUUUCCUAGACUGAUUCUUAGAGCAAGUGAAUUGAUACACAUAAAGCCCUUUAUGUAGUGCCUGACAUGUAGUGCGUCUAAUAAAGGUCAAAUAUUCUAAAUGAAAUACCGGUUCCAAAUGGAAAACUUGGAAGCGGACUCAACAUUAAAGUGAAAAGUGAUCUUUUGUAUUGUGAAGGAUUUUUCCAAAAUUGAAAUUUUUC